CAGAGUGGUCAGGUAAGACUUCUUCAAAGAGGUGAUGUUAGAGAGGAUACCAGAAAGAUAAACAGGUGUUACUUGGUGAAAGAGACCCAAGAACAGGAAGAGGAAUGUAUUCUACGAGUGUUCAUGCAGAGGGGAGUGUGAUUUUAAAACUUAGGAUAUUUAGCUCAUUUCUAUUUUCAUAUGAAAUAUCUUUAGCUUUGUUGUUCAUUUCAGAGAGAGAGAAACAGUGAUGAACCAGUCUAAGAAAGAGGGACCAGUAUGCUGAGGGCACUUCAACGUACAAGUAGACAAGUUGGAGGCCAUUUAGCUGGAAGAAAAUUCAUCAAGGCAGGGCAUGAAAGCUGGGUUCUAGUAUUGGCAGAACUUAGUAUUAUGUUGGAUCCAGCAAGUUGCCAUAGGACCAAUGAGGGGAAGUGACAAGGGGGGAAGUAACAAGGCAGGAAGUGACAAGGAGAUGGAUUUCGUUCAUGAAAACUAAAUUUUGAACAAUGCAGAGUUACAUGUUUAUUGUGAUUGUUUUGCAGUACAGUUCUCUAAUAGGGAACGUUGUCAAUUAAUGUUAGAAACACUAAAAAGGAAAAGAGUAUGAUGGGUAGGAGGGAGACAGACUUAAAGUUUAUGAAUCACUUACUAUGUACAAGACUUUGUAUUUUGCUCUUUAUGUAUUUUAUCUGAGCAAAACACAAGCUAGCUCAUGAUGUUCUCAAAGAAUACCAACAUCAGACAAAGUCACUCUGUGACCACAAUGAAAUGAGAGGAAAAAAAAUACCACUUAAUAAUCCUAAUUACGUAUAACACUGUACAAUCAGAAAAAUAUAUUGUCUUCUAGCUAAAAUGAGUGACUGAUAUGAUCUUUCUCAAUUACAGCUUUAGUCUACCUUAACAAGUAAGAUUCAUUAAGAUACCUAAUCAUGGAAUUAUUUCUAGUAAUUGACAGGACCAAAUCCAGAGCAAGCUUAGCUUUCUUGAACCCUUCCUCCUCACCUAAAAUUGCCUAAUAUGAGCCCACAUCCUAUAAUAAUUUCUAUCUAACACUCUCUUACAGAAAUGUCCCACAACUCCAGUGGUGUGUGAUCACCCACAUUGCAGCAGCUCUUAUCAGAGAGGAUUCUCAAAGGAAGAAUAUUAGGUGGGAUUCAGCACAUUAUCAGGAAAAGUAAUUGGCUUAAAUGAUGAGGGGAAACAGUGUCUCUUCGGAUUUCGGAGGUUCCAUCAAAGUGAUAAACUUCAACCCCUCCAGGCCCCGGGAAUGGCUGGGUAUAAUACUGCAAAUGAGACAUAGGAAGUAUACAGGAAGUUCUCUUCAAACUUCGGACUCCGAGCAGUGGCUGGGCUUCCAGAGUCAAGCUCUAGCAGAGCACUCCCCACCAACAAUCUCUAGGGACAUGAAUGGUGAGCAAUGGACACAGGGAACUGGAGCCAGGUAGCAGAAUUCAUCAUCUUGGGCUUCCCCCAUCUCCAGGGUGUCCAGAUUUAUCUCUUCCUCUUGUUGCUUCUCAUUUACCUCAUGACUGUGUUGGGAAACCUGCUGAUAUUCCUGGUGGUCUGCCUGGACUCCCGGCUUCACACACCCAUGUACCACUUUGUCAGCAUUCUCUCCUUCUCAGAGCUUGGCUAUACAGCUGCCACCAUCCCUAAGAUGCUGGCAAACUUGCUCAGUGAGAAAAAGACCAUUUCAUUCUCUGGGUGUCUCCUGCAGAUCUAUUUCUUUCACUCCCUUGGAGCGACUGAGUGCUAUCUCCUGACAGCUAUGGCCUACGAUAGGUAUUUAGCCAUCUGCCGGCCCCUCCACUACCCAACCCUCAUGACCCCAACACUUUGUGCAGAGAUUGCCAUUGGCUGUUGGUUGGGAGGCUUGGCUGGGCCAGUAGUUGAAAUUUCCUUGAUUUCACGCCUCCCAUUCUGUGGCCCCAAUCGCAUUCAGCACGUCUUUUGUGACUUCCCUCCUGUGCUGAGUUUGGCUUGCACUGAUACGUCUAUAAAUGUCCUAGUAGAUUUUGUUAUAAAUUCCUGCAAGAUCCUAGCCACCUUCCUGCUGAUCCUCUGCUCCUAUGUGCAGAUCAUCUGCACAGUGCUCAGAAUUCCCUCAGCUGCCGGCAAGAGGAAGGCCAUCUCCACGUGUGCCUCCCACUUCACUGUGGUUCUCAUCUUCUAUGGGAGCAUCCUUUCCAUGUAUGUGCAGCUGAAGAAGAGCUACUCACUGGACUAUGACCAGGCCCUGGCAGUGGUCUACUCAGUGCUCACACCCUUCCUCAACCCCUUCAUCUACAGCUUGCGCAACAAGGAGAUCAAGGAGGCUGUGAGGAGGCAGCUAAAGAGAAUUGGGAUAUUGGCAUGAGUUGGGGCUGAGAGUAGGCCAAGGCCGGGCCUGAGGAUAUGGUGGCCCCAGGGAUCAACAGUGGCCAGAGACGAGAAACUAAAAAUUCAGUGCUUUUCUAUGUGGGGUGGUGGAGCUGCAGCAAGUGCUGACUGACUUCCAGUGUUAUAGCGACCUUCAUACUGUCUGCUGGAGCCACAUUUGGCUUGAGACCAGAGACUAGGGAAAGUACACAUCCCUUCAACAUGAUGUAGUGCAGUGAUUUUCAAAACUCAGAUGUUUAUGUAUCACACUUAGGUUUUUUUUAAAAUCUGUGUCUUACCUAUUAUACGUUUAUAGGCAUUUUUCAAAUUUACUUGACUUAAUAUAAAUAUAGUCAGGCAUGUCCUAAACAAAAUGUGAUUCAUGAUGUUUUUUGUACCACUUGCAAUCAUUUCAUGUGGAGAAGACUGGUACAGUAGAAAAAAGCAUGUUUUUUGAACUCAUAUAUAUCUGGAUUUAAAUCAUGUUUUAUUCAGUCACUUGCUAAUUACUUAAUCUUUAGAAAGUAACUUAGCAUCUCUGAGUCUUAAUUUCAUUAUUUGAUAAUGGUAUUUUCUUGAAGAGUGUUUUGAAUAUUAACGUUAAGAUUUGUAAACCACAGUGCACAGUGUCUGACAUGUAGGUGAUAGUAAAUAAAUAAGGACUUGUUUUUAUUUAUUUUAUUCUGCGAAGACUUCACAUCAUUACUCUGGGUCUUAGAACAAUAUCUAGUAAAACAUAAAUAAACAAAAAUACUUUCCAAGUAUUUUCUCCAAAGGAAAGGAGCAAACCAGCCAGAAGGAAUACUUGUAUAGUAUACAAGUAUACUAUACUUGAAAAGUAUAGUUUGUCACAGUUCUGUUCUGACAAGUUUCAUGUACCUGUCUUAGUGGUCCUAAUAUCUAUGGCCAGUAUAAUGUAUGAAAGUAUAGGAGUUGAGUCAGUGGAAAGAAAUAGGAUUACUUUUUACAUCGAACCAUUUCUUUAUUGAAUUGUAAGCUAAUUAUUUCCUGAAACGUGUGAAAAAUAAUUCUAAAAUGUAGCAUAUGAGAGAUCUGGGGAUUCAAUUAAUAGCUAAUAUUAUGUAUUCUUUAUGUAUCCUUCCAUGAAUGGAGGAUCAAAUAUUAACUACAAGAAAUCUUUGAAUUCUAUAGAACUUCCUAAGAAGAUUACAAAAUAUUUUUAAUACCACACUUUUAAAGGUAUUCAUCCAUCCAUGCAUUCAAAUUAACACGUUUAUUUAGCUCUUACUAUAUAUCAGAUGCAGUGUCAACUCUACAAAAGCAAUGAACAAGACAUAUAUAUGUCCAGGUCCUACCUUUAGGGUGUUUUAAAAGAGUUGAGAAUAUAAAUAUUAAAAUUAUAAUUAAUUUAUAAUUAGUUAUAAUUAAUUAUAAUUGUGGGAAGUAGUAUUAAGAUAAACAUGCAUUCUCCUUUUUUUUCACUUGUCUUUGAAGUUUAUUGAGAAUUUUAAGCAGAUAAAUGUUUUUACAUUAAAUAAUCACCAG